GUUCGGGUCGUGGGGCGGAGGGAAGAGCGGGCGGGCGGGAGGCGCCGGCGCCAGACGCGGAGGGAAGGAGCUACGAGUAGCCGCCGAGAGGCCGCGGAGCCAGCGACGACCGACCCAGCCGAGCCGCCGCCGCCGCCGCGCCCCCAUGGCGGCCGCCAAGGACACUCAUGAGGACCAUGAUACUUCCACUGAGAAUACAGACGAGUCCAACCAUGACCCUCAGUUUGAGCCAAUAGUUUCUCUUCCUGAGCAAGAAAUUAAAACACUGGAAGAAGAUGAAGAGGAACUUUUUAAAAUGCGGGCAAAACUGUUCCGAUUUGCCUCUGAGAACGAUCUCCCAGAAUGGAAGGAGCGAGGCACUGGUGACGUCAAGCUCCUGAAGCACAAGGAGAAAGGGGCCAUCCGCCUCCUCAUGCGGAGGGACAAGACCCUGAAGAUCUGUGCCAACCACUACAUCACGCCGAUGAUGGAGCUGAAGCCCAACGCAGGUAGCGACCGUGCCUGGGUCUGGAACACCCACGCUGACUUCGCCGACGAGUGCCCCAAGCCAGAGCUGCUGGCCAUCCGCUUCCUGAAUGCUGAGAGUGAGCCAAGGGCCCUGGGGACCUGCCUGACUUGGGGCUCACCUGCGUGGCAGCGUGGCGGGUUAUGUGCAACAAAUGCUGUUGCCUUUUGGGGAGAGGGGGCAGUAACUGGGAAGUGUGUCGUGUGGGCUGCCCUGCCCUGCUGUUUGGGGGCCAUGCCCAGACUGAAGCCAUGAGCAGCGCCUUCCCCCUUAAACUCAAAGCUGUGCCAAGUAGCUGGUGAACAGCAGUGCCCGCUCAGCCGCCUUGUGGCUGGCACUUUGGUUUGCUCUCCAAGCUCCGGUUCCCAUUAGUUGUUGCGGAGCCUGAGGCCCAACCCAGGGCUUCCUCCCAGUGCUGAUCCUCGUGCCAGGCUUCUGGUUCACUGGGGCCAGGGGCCCCUCAUGGUUGCCUGGGUGCCAGCAGGGGCUGGGCAGAGAGAUCCACAGGCCCAGGCUGAUCUCUUCCCUGCUCAGAGGUCUUUCCAGUCCAGAUCGUCCAAGCUGCGUCCAGUGGCUCCUGGAGGAGUCAGUGGGUACUGUGGCCUGGCGCCUGGUAGCUGGCCGUUUGGUGCCAAGUGACCUUGUCCUUGCUGUGGGCGUGGCUGCCCCAGCAGCCUUUCCAACACGGUUGGGAGCCGAGCCUGUGGCAAAGAGGCCCAUGCCCCUUGGUUGCCUGAGGGUCCGUGCUCUACCGCUCUGCCCAAAUGGGUGCAGUCAGAUGAAGGAGACAGAAGGCCAGGGCCGAUGUCAGGUGGACCAGUCCUUUCUUAGGUCAGCAAUUACCAUGAAAUGGGUCUUCUGUGAAUCCUGACUCUUCAGACCCGGCAGGGCAUGUCUCUUCCACUGCUCACAGCUCUUAGGAAGUCUUCGCUCUCCCUUCCACAGAUGCACAGAAAUUCAAAA